CUCCCACUGCCGUUGUGGGUAACGCGGACGUGGAAGAACCUCGUCUGCGGAGGAAAAGGUAGAUGUUAAAUGGUAACUACGCGCGAGGUUCUGAGGAGCCCUGGGAACAGGAAGGAGAAAAGAAUACCAAAAGUGACAACAGUUUGCCAAUCGCAGUCUUUAAUCUGAUAAAGCGGUUAUCUCGUCUUGAGUCCCAGGUGCCGAGUCAAUCCCCAUACACAGCCGCCGCCAUUGCCUCGAGUCCUUGUGUCUGACUGUCUGUUCCUGCUGCUGUAUGACACAGCACCUCGAGGCAAGGAAAUAAGAAAACUGCCUCUGAUCCAAGCAGAGAAGAACUCCUGUAGCCUGUAAUACCAGCUGUGGGUACUACUCUCAGUGUUGGAGAUCAUCAAAAUACAAUUGGACCAGACCCUUUGGAAAUAAUUCUGUGUCUCAAAUGCCCUGUGGAGCACACACUUAAUCAGUUGAUGGCUAUGGAAUUUUCCAACAUCAGCUAAAGAGAAGGGCCUACUUUAAGGCUGGCCAAUUCUGCAAGAAAGGCAAGGAGGAGGAGACUGGCUCACAGCUCUGGAGGACCCCCUUCUGUCAGCUGUGGGGCUUGACACCACUUGAACAAGAAAAGGAGGGGGAAACUGCACCACAUCAGUGAAGCCGAGUGGUCCUCCAGAGCAAAGGCCAGCCUUCCUUCCAGCUGUCUGGCCAAGGAGCUUCAGGAUCUUCUAGCAAGCACCCCAGAGGCAGAAGACUGUCAUCCAUGGUACAGGACUGCGGCGAACAAGCUGACUGCGCAGUCACGUGGGGCUGACGGUGGGUCAUGUGACCAGGCUCUGCAUUAGGCCUGCCGAGAGGAGUGUUUUCUUGCAUCCAGAAAAGACCUGAGAGGCGGACGACACCUGUGCUCCGCAGAGCAGAACGUGGGAGGAACGGCGGGAUGUUAAGGUAGGAGCUCAAGAAGCAGAGAGUCUACCUGCCCGACGCGUUCGUGGAGAGGAGCAGCGGUUGCUGUUGGAGGAGGUGGGUGCAAGGACGGCAGAUGGCAUCCCUGAGAGGUGGUGACUGAGACUAGAUGCGGGUGCAGGUCUGUUUCUUUCUAGGUUCCUGUAGAGAUCUGUAUGUAGCUGUUCACUUGGAAGUUAAUUAAGAAAGAACAAAAACUAUUCAUUUGGAUUCAAGGUCCAUCUCCACUGGUGGCUGUGGUGGCUUUGGAUUGUUGGAAGACCAUCACCUUCAGCAGGUCUGCACUUGGGAACAAUCAUUCUCCCCCAGCCCGAGCGUGCCUCUGCCCUCUGUAUCAUUGACAGAGGCUGUAUGUUUGGAAAGAGAACUUUGUGACUGCAGAACUGACAGUUGACUCUAAUUCUUGCUACCAAGUUUUUCCCCGACCCAGUGAAAGAGUGUUAAGACUUCGACCUAGGACACAUUGAGAACCAAGGCCAAGACUGGACAGGGCCAUAUAACUGGGCUUCAACCAUGGCUGGGACUAAGAAUAAGACAAGAGCCCAGGCCAAAACUGAAAAAAAGGCUGCUAUACAAGCUAAAGCUGGAGCAGAGAGGGAGGCUACUGGUGUUGUUAGGCCUGUAGCCAAGACCAGGGCCAAAGCAAAAGCCAAGACAGGGUCUAAGACAGAUGCAGUAGCAGAGAUGAAGGCAGUGUCUAAGAACAAGGUUGUUGCUGAGACGAAGGAAGGAGCUCUGUCAGAGCCUAAGACUCUGGGCAAAGCCAUGGGAGAUUUCACUCCCAAGGCUGGGAAUGAGUCCACCAGCUCCACAUGUAAAAAUGAGGCUGGUACUGAUGCCUGGUUCUGGGCUGGGGAAGAGGCCACUAUCAAUUCCUGGUUCUGGAAUGGAGAAGAGGCUGGUAAUAGUUUCAGCACUAAGAAUGAUAAACCUGAAAUUGGUGCCCAGGUCUGUGCUGAGGAGUUGGAACCUGCGGCUGGGGCCGAUUGCAAACCUAGGUCAGGGGCUGAGGAGGAGGAGGAAGAGAAUGUUAUUGGGAACUGGUUUUGGGAAGGAGAUGAUACUAGUUUUGACCCUAAUCCUAAACCUGUGAGCAGGAUAGUUAAGCCUCAGCCUGUGUAUGAAAUUAAUGAAAAAAAUAGGCCCAAGGACUGGUCUGAGGUAACUAUCUGGCCCAAUGCCCCUGCUGUAACUCCAGCUGUGUUAGGAUUUAGAUCCCAGGCACCAUCUGAGGCAAGCCCUCCUUCAUAUAUUGUUCUGGCCUCCGCUGAAGAAAAUGCCUGUUCUUUGCCUGUGGCAACAGCUUGCCGCCCUUCUAGGAACACUCGCUCAUGCUCACAGCCUAUCCCUGAGUGUCGUUUUGAUUCUGACCCCUGCAUCCAGACCAUAGAUGAGAUUAGACGUCAAAUCAGGAUCAGGGAGGUAAAUGGGAUUAAGCCAUUUGCUUGUCCUUGCAAAAUGGAAUGCUAUAUGGAUUCUGAGGAAUUUGAAAAACUUGUUAGCUUACUUAAGUCAACUACUGAUCCUCUUAUUCAUAAAAUAGCACGGAUUGCAAUGGGUGUCCAUAAUGUUCACCCAUUUGCCCAAGAGUUUAUUAACGAAGUAGGUGUAGUGACACUUAUUGAAAGCUUGCUCAGUUUUCCUUCCCCUGAAAUGAGAAAAAAGACUGUAAUUACUCUGAAUCCUCCUUCUGGGGAUGAAAGACAACGCAAAAUUGAAUUACAUGUUAAGCAUAUGUGUAAAGAAACCAUGUCAUUUCCUUUGAACUCACCGGGACAGCAAUCUGGAUUAAAGAUACUAGGACAACUGACUACUGAUUUUGUCCAUCACUACAUUGUUGCCAAUUACUUUUCAGAGCUUUUCCAUUUGCUGUCCUCAGGAAAUUGCAAAACCAGAAAUCUUGUUUUGAAACUACUUUUAAAUAUGUCUGAAAAUCCAACUGCAGCCAGAGACAUGAUCAAUAUGAAGGCAUUGGCAGCAUUAAAACUCAUCUUUAACCAGAAAGAGGCAAAAGCCAAUCUUGUUAGUGGUGUGGCCAUAUUUAUUAACAUAAAGGAGCAUAUCAGAAAAGGCUCAAUUGUAGUUGUUGAUCACUUGAGUUAUAAUACACUCAUGGCCAUUUUCAGGGAAGUUAAAGAGAUUAUUGAAACAAUGUAAAAUGAGCCAGAGAUAGAACAUUUUAAGCCAUCUUCAAACUCUAGCAGGCUGUACAUUACAGUGUACACAUUAUACACUGCAUCUUUAACACAGAGUCACCUGUGACAGGCUCUAGGUUUGAGCUAGACUAUUUUGGGGGUAUCAAAUGAAUAUUAUACCUUGGGCUGAAAAUGUUUGAUUUUUAUCUUGUCUAGAUUGGCAUAUUUUUAACAUUUUACUUAAGAUAGCAAACCAGUUCGUUUUAAGUAAGCUAACUUGUUCAUUAGUAUCUGUGGCUUAAAAUGGCAAAAAAGAAAAUAUCCUUGAGUUUGUAAUCUAGUUACAGAAGUAAGGCAUACACACACACAAAGAUAACAGUACCUAGAGAGAGAGUGUGUGUGAGUGUGCGUGUCUCUGUGUGUGCACGUGCACGCUCAUGGCCAAAUGUGCGCACUCUACAUAAAGGAGGCAGGAGUUCCUAUAGGCUAUUUAAUGUAAGAGAAACUAUUUUUCUCCUGUUCCAGCUGUAUCAGAUACUCGUUCCGCAACACAGAAAUGACUCAGAAUCUCAGACAAAAUGUAUUAUUUGUUCAAUUUUAAUUUUGCUACUACAUUCAUAACUCUUAAAUUGUUAGGCUGUUUCAUUUACAUCAAAGUUAUCUCACAAAAGAGAAGGCAGGAAACGUUUUGUGAGUGCCUAUUCUAUGUCAAACACUGUGUUGGCACCAUAUUUUACAAGUUUUUUUCCUCUUCUCACAGUGAUCUUGUGAGUUAGUUACUUAUAUUUUUAUUAGAACUCAUUAUUCUGGGUACCCUCCAAUGAGAAUUAGAGAGGUUAAAUACCUUUUCCUAGAUUCCCACAGCAGGAAGGUGGCAUAGCUGUUUUGUCUGACACCAGAACCCAUCUCACCACACUGCUUUACAGUCUUCCUGAAGGACAUUUUGAGGUGGGGGGGCCUUCAAAGCUCAGAGACUGGUUUGAAUGGUUUAAUUUUGCAAUGGAUCAUGUCCAUGCCAGGUGUUACAAUUCUUAACUUCCUCCAAAUUCGUGUGUCCAUUAGACAUUUGGCUACAUCUGGCUGGAGGUCAGGAGAAAAUUCUGAGGUAAAUAGAUGGAUUUUAUCUGGCAGUGUCGAAAAUAGUAGGAGCCUAAAACUUUGUUCAAUGAGUAAGAUGUAGAUUUGGAGUCAUCAGCAGGGGAAACUUGUUAGAUGUCCUUUGUAUCUUUUUCUAUCCAUUUGUAUUUUUUCUUUCCCAAAGAGCUGAAAUCAUUUUAUACCCUGAAUUUAAAAGGUAAUUGCUUUUUUCCUCCUUGCGAAAUCAUACCUUAAUUUUUUUUUUUUUUUUUUUUACCAUUUAUGAUUUAUUCUCCUAUGUGUCAUAUGAAAGGCCAAGGGGCUUUAUCUUUUACUAGUAGGCAAGCCUGGGCAUUUCUGCAUUUGUGCCAGCUAACACUACAAAAUAGACUUAAUUAGAGAAAUUUAGACCCAGAAUUGCAGCUUCAACAACACAAAACAGGAAAGCUAGAAGAGGUUGCUGUGUCAACCUACAAGAUAGUGAUUCUUGGAAGUUGGUAUGGACCAGAAAGCAUUCCCAGGACAUUUAGGCUAUGGCUGAGUUCUCUAAGACUCAGGGUGGGAAUUAUAAUCCCUGGUCUAAGCUGAUAUGAAAGUUUCUAUGUGUGAAAAUAUGGAGUUAUAUGCUUUGAGAUUUUCUGCCAGUUAAACUAAAACAAGAUCAUACUGUAAAUGUUUGUAACUUGCUUCCCCCCACUGUAUACUGUAAACAUCUUUGCAUGUCAAUAAAUAUGCCUCUACAACAUAUUUUUGAAUCACUUAAUAUUUUUCCCAUGUUAACAGUUGGUAUAUAGUGUUGUAAACCUUUAUUGCAUAUUCUCAUAACAUACAAUAUACACAUUCUUUUGCAAAAAUGGGAACACAGUAUUGAGACUUGCCUUUUCCUCUUAACACUUAUCUUUUCAAUUUAGUAUUAUAUAGAUCUGUCACAUGCUUUUUAUCUAAUAACUUUAUAGAAAUAUAAUUGCCAUACAUUAAGCUGCAUGUUGAAAGUAUACAGUGUGAUCAGUUUUGGAAUGUAUAUACACACAAAACCAUAACCACAAUCAAAAUUGUAAAUACAUUCAUCACCCACCAAAGCUACUUUUUUUUUGAGACAGAGUCUUGCUCUGUCACCCAGGCUGGAGUACAGUGGCGCAAUCUCGGCCCACUGCAACCUCUGCUUCCCAGGUUCAAGUGAUUCUCGUGCCUUAGCCUCCUGAGCAGCUGGGACUACAGGUGCAUGCCACCACAUCCGACUAAUUUUUUUUUUUAUUUUUUGUAUUUUUAGUAGAGACAGGGUUUCACCAUGUUGGCCAGGCUGGUCUUGAACUCCUGGUCUCAAGUGAUCUACCCAUCUUGGUCUCCCUGAGUGCCAGGAUUACAGGCGUGAGCCACCAUGCCCAGCCUCCCCCAAAGCUUCUUAAUGCCCUUUUGUAAUCCCUCCCUCCCCUCUCUCCCUGUGCCCCUAACCCAGGCAACCAUGGGACAUUUUCUGACAAAAUAGAAUUGUUUUCAUUUCCUGUAAUUGUGUAUAAAUGGACUCAUAUAGCAUGUACUCUUUGGUCGGGAGGGGAUCUGGCUUAUUUCACUUAGUGUAAUUAUUUGAGAUUCAUCCAUAUCAUGUGUCUCACUAUUUCAUUGCUUUUUAUUGCCAAGUAGUAUUCCACCAUAUGGCUUUACCACAGUUUAUUUAUCCAUUCACUUAUUGAUGGACAUUUGGGCUGUUCAGAGUUUGGCCAUUAUAAGUAAAGCAGCUAUGAGCAUUUGUGUACAAGUGUUUUUAUGGACAUAGGCUUUCAUAUCUUUGGAAUGACAUCUAACAAUAUUGAAUCUUCGACCCAUGAAUAAAAUCUCUCUCCACUUA